UCCACAACUGAAACAUCCACUUCUGAACACCAUGUCCUACUACAGCCAUCUUUCUGGUGGCCUGGGCUGCGGCUUGGCUGUGGCUGUGACUAUGGGAAGGACUGUGGCUGUGGCUGAGUAUGGCAGGUGCAGACAUGGCUGCCACUCAUCUUACUCUGCCAGGUAAUGACACCAUGGAUUCCACUGAGGAACACCUAGAGCAGUUCAGUCUACUGCACUCCUCC